GGGGAGGCGCGUGCGCACUGGCGUGCGAGACUCGGCGGGCGCUGUUGAGGGAGUCGGGCCGCGACUGUGGUCGUUUUUAUACCUUCCCGCGCGGACGCCGGCGCUGCCAACGGAAGGGCGGGUAGGGCGGUGCGUGAUUAGGUUGGCGAAGGCUCUGCUGCCAUGAAGGUGAAGAUUAAGUGCUGGAACGGCGUGGCCACUUGGCUCUGGGUGGCCAACGAUGAGAACUGUGGCAUCUGCAGGAUGGCAUUUAACGGAUGCUGCCCUGACUGUCCUCUCCAUGGAGAAAGCAUUUCUAGGUGUUUGGGCUGGUGCCCGCAGCCUGUGCCUGUCCUGGGAGGCAGGGCCCAUCCACAGGUGCCCAUCAACACAGCUUCCCCAACGCCUGGGCAGCACACCGGAUCCCUGAUGUCUAGGGAAGAGUCUUCUAGGUCCCCAGACCCCACCCCUCCUGCCCUUGAUCAAGAGACCAGUUCACUACUCAGAUGCACGUCUCCUUGGUGCCUUGACCAUUCAUGUGACCUUUUUGGCAUCACAGAUCAAGUGUCUGCAGAUGGGCCCAGGGCCUGUAGGCAAGGUGCCCGGCGACGACUGCCCGCUGGUGUGGGGCCAGUGCUCCCACUGCUUCCACAUGCAUUGCAUCCUCAAGUGGCUGCACGCACAGCAGGUGCAGCAGCACUGCCCCAUGUGCCGCCAGGAAUGGAAGUUCAAGGAGUGAGGCCCGACCUGGCUCUCGCUGGAGGGGCAUCCUGAGACUCCUUCCUCAUGCUGGCGCCGAUGGCUGCUGGGGACAGCGCCCCUGAGCUGCAACAAGGUGGAAACAAGGGCUGGAGCUGCGUUUGUUUUGCCAUCACUAUGUUGACACUUUUAUCCAAUAAGUGAAAACUCAUUAAACUACUCAAAUCUUGCUGGAGGCCUCUGGGUGCCUGUGUUCUCGGCAUAUAGAUGUGGUCUCGGUGUGUUUUGAUAUGAAAACUCUCAUGAAUAAACAUCUCCGUGAAACGCCAAGGCCCUCGUCAAACCCUGAGUCAUGACUGGGAGGAGAAGGAGCAGGAUCAGACGGUAGAGCCUGGGGCAUGCUCUUCAGGCAUGCUCUUGCCUGCUGGAUUGCCGGCGGCGGCCCUGGGACCCUCCCUCAGGCUGGCUCUGAGGGACCCUGGCUGUGCAAAGCUGGCGGCCACUGCUU